GACUGCGCGCGACAACUCCUCGGGCAGAGGGGGUUGAGUCAGCCCCGCCGCCGGGGAAGCAGCUCCGGGCCGAGCCCCUGAGUCAGAACCGGCCCGUGGAGGCAGCCGGUGCCCCAGCCCGCAGCUUCGUCGCCCAACCGAGGCUCCCAGGGCUGGCGGCCGGGAUCUGAGGGGCCUGGACGUGGGGAUGUUCAGGGAUCCAGGAGGAGGACUUUCACGGGCCAUCCAAGCCACCCCCUCCUCUGGAGGAGGCCUCUUCUCUGUGGGCUCCCUCAAGACACCACCUCCCCAUCGCCGCAAAGUCCAUCCCUACCCGCCUUCCCCUCCCCUUGCGAGUGGUCCCGCUUACCCUUCACUGCCAUCAUCGCCCUGCCUUUCCCAGUCCUGCUGGCUGCGCUCAGUCUUUAGGUGGUAGCAGGCCAGGUACAGCGGACACUUGCUGAUGGGGGAUUCCAGGAGGUGGGAUUUCAAGUGGCACCACUGCAAGUGGAGGUGAGAACGAGCGUGAGGACCUGGAGCAGGAGUGGAAGCCCCCGGAUGAGGAGUUGAUCAAGAAACUGGUGGAUCAGAUCGAAUUCUACUUUUCUGAUGAAAACCUGGAGAAGGACGCCUUUUUGCUAAAACACGUGAGGAGGAACAAGCUGGGAUAUGUGAGCGUUAAGCUACUCACAUCCUUCAAAAAGGUGAAACAUCUUACACGGGACUGGAGAACCACAGCACAUGCUUUGAAGUAUUCAGUGGUCCUUGAGUUGAAUGAGGACCACCGGAAGGUGAGGAGGACCACCCCCGUCCCACUGUUCCCCAACGAGAACCUCCCCAGCAAGAUGCUCCUGGUCUAUGAUCUCUACUUGUCUCCUAAGCUGUGGGCUCUGGCCACCCCCCAGAAGAAUGGAAGGGUGCAAGAGAAGGUGAUGGAACACCUGCUCAAGCUUUUUGGGACUUUUGGAGUCAUCUCAUCAGUGCGGAUCCUCAAACCUGGGAGAGAGCUGCCCCCUGACAUCCGGAGGAUCAGCAGCCGCUACAGCCAAGUGGGGACCCAGGAGUGCGCCAUCGUGGAGUUCGAGGAGGUGGAAGCAGCCAUCAAAGCCCAUGAGUUCAUGAUCACAGAAUCUCAGGGCAAAGAGAACAUGAAAGCUGUCCUGAUUGGUAUGAAGCCACCCAAAAAGAAACCUGCCAAAGACAAAAAUCAUGACGAGGAGCCCACUGCGAGCAUCCACCUGAACAAGUCCCUGAACAAGAGAGUCGAGGAGCUUCAGUACAUGGGUGAUGAGUCUUCUGCCAACAGCUCCUCUGACCCCGAGAGCAACCCCACAUCCCCUAUGGCGGGCCGACGGCACGCGGCCACCAACAAGCUCAGCCCGUCUGGCCACCAGAAUCUCUUUCUGAGUCCAAAUGCCUCCCCGUGCACAAGUCCUUGGAGCAGCCCCUUGGCCCAACGCAAAGGCGUUUCCAGAAAGUCCCCACUGGCGGAGGAAGGUAGACUGAACUGCAGCACCAGCCCUGAGAUCUUCCGCAAGUGUAUGGAUUAUUCCUCUGACAGCAGCGUCACUCCCUCUGGCAGCCCCUGGGUCCGGAGGCGUCGCCAAGCCGAGAUGGGGACCCAGGAGAAAAGCCCCGGUACGAGUCCCCUGCUCUCCCGGAAGAUGCAGACUGCAGAUGGGCUACCCGUAGGGGUGCUGAGGUUGCCCAGGGGUCCUGACAACACCAGAGGAUUUCAUGGCCAUGAGAGGAGCAGGGCCUGUGUAUAAAUACCUUCUAUUUUUAAUACAAGCUCCACUGAAAACCACCUUCGUUUUCAAGGUUCUGACAAACACCUGGCAUGACAGAAUGGAAUUCGUUCCCCUUUGAGAGAUUUUUUAUUCAUGUAGACCUCUUAAUUUAUCUAUCUGUAAUAUACAUAAAUCGGUACGCCAUGGUUUGAAGACCACCUUCUAGUUCAGGACUCCUGUUCUUCCCAGCAUGGCCACUAUUUUGAUGAUGGCUGAUGUGUGUGAGUGUGAUGGCCCUGAAGGGCUGUAGGACGGAGGUUCCCUGGGGGAAGUCUGUUCUUUGGUAUGGAAUUUUUCUCUCUUCUUUGGUAUGGAAUUUUUCCCUUCAGUGACUGAGCUGUCCUCGAUAGGCCAUGCAAGGGCUUCCUGAGAGUUCAGGAAAGUUCUCUUGUGCAACAGCAAGUAGCUAAGCCUAUAGCAUGGUGUCUUGUAGGACCAAAUCGAUGUUACCUGUCAAGUAAAUAAAUAAUAAAACACCCAACUGGGAGUGCUGACUUUGAGGUUAUAGAUUGUGCCUGACAAAAGUCUGUGCCUGUCUGACAGAGCUGUGGGUGGUAUGUCAUGAGGCCCUGAGGAGCUUAGCAGAGACAUCUUUCUUUUCUUUAAGAGAACAUUUAAAAAUUUUUUUAUUUGUACACAUUUAUGGGCUACAUGAGAAACUUUGUUACAUGUUUAUAAUGCAUAGUGAUCAAGUCAGGGCAUUUAGGGUUUCUCACUGUACCCCAGGGCAGCCCCAGGGCUCUCCUUGGGCUUCUGGCAGCCUGAGUGGUGUCUCAUCACAGGGAAUUUUACUGAGCAAAGGCAGCUUGGCGUAUACUGAGGGUGUACAGUCCAGGACCCACAGCAUUGAUCUCACCUGGGAACUUAUUAGAAAUCCAGAUUCUCAGGCCAACCCUAGGCCCACUGAAUUAGAAAGUCUGGGAGAAAGGCCUGGAAUUUGGGUUUUAACAAACGCUGCAGGUGAUUCUGAUGCACGCUGGAGAACCACUGGAUGGACAAAGGCUGCAGGACUUGAGGUCAGUCCAUUUGACCCCCAAUCUCUCACUAUUUUGUGACCUUGGGAAGGUUACUAAGCCCCGUGAACCUCAUCAUCUCCCUGUGAAUUGCUUUGUUACGAUGUCCAUGUCUGGAAUGCAGCUGGCCCUCCAUAAAUGUUAGCUCUCUUUCCUUCUCACUUGGGUUAAUGUUUGUUAUCAUCAGGAGCUGCCUUGGUGUAGCAGAAAGAGCAUUGGCCUAGAUUCCAGUGUUGGCUUAUGCUCUGGCUAUUUGGCAGGAUUUAAUAGAGCUUGUUAAUAAUUAUUGAACAGUGAUUAGGUGCCAGGGACUAUGCUAAGAGCUUUCCAUGCAUUAUCUCAUUUAAUCUGCCCAAAAACUACAAGAGAAAUGUUCAGGUAUUAUCUCUAUUUUAUUCCAGAAAAAAACAGACUUUACUUGGGUAAUUAACUUGUCUAAGGCUUAACAGCUAAAUUGGUAGAGUUGGGCUUGAAACUAGUGGUCUGGCUUUGGAGCCCACACUGUUUAACCACUAAGUGGUACUCAACAUUUCUGAUCUUUACUAUCCAUAUUCAAAAAAGAAUCCACCAUAAAAGGUGCUAAUAUUUAUUCAGCACCUUCCUACGUGCUAGGCAUUGGGUUAGACACAUUUCACUUACUCUCAGUGUCCAUCAUAAGGAAUUAUUAUGCCAGUAUCACACAUGCAGCUGCUGAAGUAGGAAAAUAAUAUCCCAAACUUGUGAAAAUGGACAAAGAUAGUAUAUCCUAAAUGAUAUGGCUCUAUACAAAUUAGCAGGUGAUUGUGAUCUGGAUAGUAAGAUGCUUUGUCCCUUAAGAUGCAGAAGAGUUCGUGUUAACUGGCAAAUGCCUCCAGCAAUGUUCUGGAUUUGCCAUUUCCAGCACUACCAGCUGUAGGUAGCCUGAAGGCUUGUGCCUAGACCACCAGGACUCCUGACCUUGGGCAAUGUCAGGGCCCCCUCCAGCCCCGCCCUAUGCUUCCCUCCCUGACUCUGCUCCCAUCACCCCCUGCCUGCUCCUUCCCUGCAGCCACUCCACCUGCUCCUUGGCCAUCGGGCCAUCUGGGCUUCACCAGCUCUUCUUGGCCUGUGACAUUCAAGGCUGUUCCACCCUAUUAUGCCUGUUACACAAGUCACAGCUCUAUUUUUAGAUUAACCCUCGUGGAUCAUAGUUACUUUUAAAAAUACCUACACCCUCACCUUUACAUGUGAAUACAGAUGAACUUGGCCUUCCUUUGGUCGUAUUGCCCUGUGUGACAUUAUAAAAGAACCCUGAAGUGGGGGUCAGCAGAUCUGAGGUCGAGUCGUGGCUUUUCUACUAAGCAACUGUGACCUUCAGCAAGUCAUUUAUUUUAUUGGUUCACAGUUCUUCCCACAAACCAGUGGAUAACAAGAAGAUGUUCCUUAAAUAAGGUCAUAUAUGUGCAAGUGCUUUCUGAAUGGAAAAGUGCUUUGCAGGCAUUAGUCACUACUUAUCCUGCUGUCUGAUCAUCACCUCCAAAGGCAAGCCUCCUUUUGCUGCAAUUCUUAACCCUGGCCUCACAUUAGAGUCACCUAAAGAGCUUUUAAAAACUGCCUAUGGGGCUGGGCACGGUGGCUCACGCCUGUAAUCCCAGCACUUCAGGAGACUGAGGCGGGCAGAUCAUGAGGUCAGGAGAUUGAGACUAUCCUGGCUAAUGUGGUAAAACCCUGUCUCUACUAAAAAUACAAAAAAAUUAGCCGGGCAUGGUGGCACGCACCUGUAAUCCCAGCUACUUGGGAGGCGGAGGCAGGAGAAUUGCUUGAACCUGGGAGGCGGAGGUUGCAGUGAGCCGAGAUCACGCCGCUGCAUUCCAGCCUGGGCAACAGAAUGAGACUCCAUCUCAAAAAAAUAAAAAUAAAAAUAAACAAA